ACCACUGUGGUUCUACUAUGCCUUCUGACCCCGUCUUGGACUUCAACUGGGAGAAUGUGGAGCCAUUUGAACAGGCUCCUCUUCUGGAGCAUAUUUUCUUCUGUCACUUGUAGAAAAGCUGUAUUGGAUUGUGAGGCAAUGAAAACAAAUGAAUUCCCUUCUCCAUGUUUGGACUCAAAGACUAAGGUGGUUAUGAAGGGUCAAAAUGUAUCUAUGUUUUGUUCCCAUAAGAACAAAUCACUGCAGAUCACCUAUUCAUUGUUUCGACGUAAGACACACCUGGGAACCCAGGAUGGAAAAGGUGAACCUGCGAUUUUUAACCUAAGCAUCACAGAAGCCCAUGAAUCAGGCCCCUACAAAUGCAAAGCCCAAGUUACCAGCUGUUCAAAAUACAGUCGUGACUUCAGCUUCACGAUUGUCGACCCGGUGACUUCCCCAGUGCUGAACAUUAUGGUCAUUCAAACAGAAACAGACCGACAUAUAACAUUACAUUGCCUCUCAGUCAAUGGCUCGCUGCCCAUCAAUUACACUUUCUUUGAAAACCAUGUUGCCAUAUCACCAGCUAUUUCCAAGUAUGACAGGGAGCCUGCUGAAUUUAACUUAACCAAGAAGAAUCCUGGAGAAGAGGAAGAGUAUAGGUGUGAAGCUAAAAACAGAUUGCCUAACUAUGCAACAUACAGUCACCCUGUCACCAUGCCCUCAACAGGCGGAGACAGCUGUCCUUUCUGUCUGAAGCUACUACUUCCAGGGUUAUUACUGUUGCUGGUGGUGAUAAUCCUAAUUCUGGCUUUUUGGGUACUGCCCAAAUACAAAACAAGAAAAGCUAUGAGAAAUAAUGUGCCCAGGGACCGUGGAGACACAGCCAUGGAAGUUGGAAUCUAUGCAAAUAUCCUUGAAAAACAAGCAAAGGAGGAAUCUGUGCCAGAAGUGGGAUCCAGGCCGUGUGUUUCCACAGCCCAAGAUGAGGCCAAACACUCCCAGGAGCUACAGUAUGCCACCCCCGUGUUCCAGGAGGUGGCACCAAGAGAGCAAGAAGCCUGUGAUUCUUAUAAAUCUGGAUAUGUCUAUUCUGAACUCAACUUCUGAAAUUUACAGAAACAAACUACAUCUCAGGUAGAGACAGGGUUUUGCCAUGUUGGCCAGGCUGGUCUUCAACUCCUGACCUCAAGUGAUCCGCCCACCUCGGACUCCCAAAGUGCUGGGAUUACAGGCGUGAGCCACCUCGCCUGGCCCUCCAUUUCCUGAUCUAGUCUUAUAUCCACGCUCACCACCUCAGCACGCUCAGACCCACGCUGCUGUGGGCUCCUCUGGCUCCUGGAAGAGUGCGUCCGCAGAUGCUGCAGUCUUUGUGUGGCUCAGCAAUUGCCACUCACAUCAGGAACUGCCUUUACCCUGUCAGGCUCUACUGAGACCCGACCCUGGUUAUUAAGCUAUAGGGGAGACAAGGAUGGAUCUUAAAGAAGACAAGCAAAAUGUAGUGAAGCAAAUAGAAUGGUGGUUCCUGGGGGAUGGGGGCAGGGGACAACGAGGAGUGACUGGCUAACAGAUACAGCGUUUCAGUUUGGAAAGACAAAAAAGUUCUGGAAAAAAGAUGGAAGGUGGUGAUGGUUGCACAAUAAUAUGAGUUUUGUUGUUGUUGUUUUUUGAGACAGAGUCUCUCUCUGUUGCCCAGGCUGGAGUGCAGGGGCACGAUUUCGGCUCACUGCAACCUCUGCCUCCCGGGUUCAAGCGAUUCUUGUGCCUCAGCCUCCCAAGUAGCUGGGAUUACAGGCACCCACCACCAUGCCCAGCUAAUUUUUGUAUUUUUAGUAAAGAUGAGGUUUCACCAUGUUGGCCAGGCUGGUCUCAAACUCCUGACCUCAAAUGAUUGGCCUGCCUUGGCCUCCCAAAGUGCUGGGAUUACAGGCAUGAGCUAUUGCGCCCGGCAAUAUGAAUGAAUGUUUUUAAUACCAUUGAAUUACACACCUAAAAUUGGUUAAAAUGGUAAAAAAUUUUAUGUUAUGUAUAACUUACCACAAUAAUUUAAAAAAUAUUGUGAAGCGCCUGCCUCAUGUGAGGUCUUCUAAUAAGAGGGGCUGUUCUCCUUCUCAAGAGCGCUCGCGGGCAUUGGGAGUUUCUUAUUCUCAAAUGUCCACAUCCCAAGGCCUACCCCGUCCCUGUCAGUGUCAGAAGUUAGCAGAGCAGAACUGCUAGAUGUGCUCACUCCAUCUCCUCCAUGGUUGGCCCACCCUUUCGAUCAGAUCCUGGAAUUGGCUUUCAGCACAGCCUUCCAGCUGGCUGUGAUAAAUGAGAGUGGCUUAAACCCUGUCAUCAGGGUUUCACAGCUUGCCCUGAACCGUAGCCUCUCAUUUUCUCCUUGCAAAUCUUCUAAGGCAGCUAAGAGAAGCCAAUUAACUUCACAAUCCACAUAAUUAGCAUUGCCCCAAACCUUUCAAGUGCUGGAAUGCUGGCGUCCACUAGUGCCUCAUUUCUUUCUAAACCUCAUUCCACAUGGCAGGGGAAGGUCUUAGGAAUUGUGGAGCUGUGGCGUUCUAAGGGUUCUCACUGCCUACCUAUCACCAGCAAGGGAGUCCUUGUUGCCAUCCAUCCCUAGGGGGUAAUUUUGUUCCCUGAGGCUGCUUUCUAGGGACUUCUGGUCGCUUGUUUUAUCCUGGACCAGACCUGAAAGCAGAGCCUGAAAUAAGGCCUUCUAUGCACAUCAUUUAUGUAGGAGGUGGCCCUAGGAAGCAGGCCCAAUGCGCCAUGGGAAAAACCAGUACCAGGGUGUUUUGCUGAGUUGAGCACUGUGGUGGGCAGCUGGACAUGAGCCCACUGGAAUCUUCUGAAGAGCCCAAGAGCCUCUUCUCAGUAUUGUCCACUUGAGGAUUGAUAGUGAGAGGCAUUUAUCCACUGGUGUCCAACGCUCACUGGUUGAGGAUCACCCCAGAAAGCGACACCUCCCCCACUUCUAGACUAGCAUGUGGGUAUUCCAAGCAGGCUUACCUCAGUGUCUCACCCCAGGCACUGCAAACACCCCAGGACAGAAAGUGAACAUGUGUAUUGUGCAAUUGAAGCAAGACACUAUCAGUGCAAAGUGAGUAGACCCUCAGAUGCUGCUGGGUCAGAGGGAAGGCCCAGGGAUAUGACACAGGACACAGAGGUGGCAGAUACACCACCUCCCAACAUUUCCUCUAUCACAGCAACUAGAACAAUGGCAACAAUAGGGGUGGGUGUGGUGGCUCACGCCUAUAAUCCCAAUACCCUGGGAGGCCAAGGCAGAAGGAUUGCUUGAGCCCAGGAGUUCAAGACUAGCCUGGGCAACUUGGCGAAACCCUGUCUCUACAAACAUAUUUGUAUGUGAUUGAACAAGUAGAACAAUGGAACGGAAAGUCCAGAUGUAGUUCUAAAUAUGUACAGGAACUUAGUAUAGGAUAAAUAUGGCAUCUUAAAUCAAUGGGGAAAAGAUGGAUUAUUCAACAUAUUGUAAAAACUUGAGAAUCACAUUAAAAAAGUUGGACUCCUACCUCAUUCUUUACAACAAAAUUAAUUCUGAUAGAUGUAGUCACAGAAGAGCUAGAAGAAUAUGCAGGGGAUUUAAAAAUAAUCUUGAAGUGGGGAGGACUUUUAUAGGUAUGACUCACAACCCAGAAAACAUAAAGGAUUGUUAAAUUUAAUUAGAUAAAUCAUUUAAUUAGAUGAAACAUUUAAAAAUUACAUUUAGAAAUCAUAAACUAAAUCCAAAGAAUAACUAGGGGCCGGGCGCAGUGGCUCACGUCUGUAAUCCCAUGGGGCAGGUGGAUCACCUGAGGUUGGGAGUUUGAGACCAGCCUGUCCAACACGGUGAAACCCCGUCUCUACUAAAAAUACAAAAAUUAGUUGGUGUGGUGGCACAUACCUGUAGUCCCUGCUACUGGGGAGGCUGAGGCAUGAGAAUUGCUUGAACCUGGGAGGUGGAGGUUGCAGUGAGCCAAGAUCGCGCCACUGCAUUCCAGCCUGGGCGACAGAGCAAGACUCCAUCUCAAAAAAAAAAAAAAAAAAAAAAAAAAAAAAAAGAAUAACUAGGGAGAAAACACCAUGAUGUGUUGCAUAAUAACAUUUCAGUCAUUCAUGGACCAAAUAUAAAAUGGGGUCCCAAAAAACUAUAAUACCGUGUUUUUACUGUACCUUUUCUAUGUUUAGACACAUUUAGAUACACAAAUACUUACCAUUGUGCUACAAUUGCCUAGUGUUCAGUAGCAUGCUGUACAGGUUUAUCCCUAGGAAGAAUAGACUAUCCCACACACCCUAGGCGUGUAGCAGGCUAUGCCAUCUAGGUUUGUGUGAGUACACUCUAUGCUGUUCAAACAGUGACCUCCACUGUUAGGUGAAGCAUGACUGUAUUUUGAGCCCAGGUCUCAGAUAUUGUAUGAAGUUUCAUAAUAUUAUGAGCUUUUACAAAUCAUUAAGAGAAAGACCAAUAAUCCAGUAGAAAACUGGGAAAAGGUGGCAUCUGCAGGGUAACACCAGGGCAGCACAGAAAUCUUGCUGGGAUGAGGAGCUGCAAACAUGUGUGGUCGACUUUUUGGCCUUCUGCCUCUUCUACUCUCAGGGAUGGGGGAUUACAACUAAAGAAGUUGUCUUUUGGCCGGGCGUGGUGGCUCACGCCUGUAAUCCCAGCACUUUGGGAGGCCGAGGCGGGUGGAUCACAAGGUCAGGAGAUCAAGACCAUCCUGGCUAACACGAUGAAACCCCGUCUCUACUAAAAAAUUCAAAAACAUUGGCCGGGCGAGGUGGCGGGCACCUGUAGUCCCAGCUACUCGGGAGGCUGAGGCAGAAGAAUUGUGUGAACCCGGGAGGCGGAGCUUGCAGUGAGCCCAGAUCGCGCCACUGCACUCCAGCCUGGGCGACAGAGGAAGGCUCCGUCUCAAAAAAAAAAAAAAAAGAAGAAGUUAUCUUUUCUCAGUGUUGCUUCUCCCUAAGGAUUUAAAGGGGAGACCUGGCCAGAGGAAUCAUCAACAGUGGAUUUGUGAUGACUGGAGUUCAUUUCCUUCUUUCUCAACUGUCCUGGAAGGAAAUGGACUAGUGCCUUACCUCUGACUCUUCCGCAGCACACACCCACCACCAGAGACAGUAACUGAGAUCUGCAGUAGCACAGAAACUUACAGGUUAGAAAAAUUAGACACCUAAGGAUUUCAUGACUCCAGACCUGUUUCCUUAGCAUAAUACCACACCAGUAGGAGAAAUACAACUUACGAAAUUUCUUUGUAAAUAAAUUCUAUAACAUUUUGGGUAAAAAUUUAUCAUAAAAAAAUUAUUAAAAGCAAUUGGGUUGGAAGGAAGUUCUGUCAAAAUACAAUCCAGGUGUGCAGUUCUCUGAUAAAUUUAGCAGUGGUUACUACUGAGGCAGUCUCAAAAAAAAGUGUAAAAGGACUUUAAGGGGUGAUGAAAAUUUUCUACAUUGCCUUUGUGGAGAUGGUUAUACAUUUGUCAAUACUCAUCAAUUUGUACAUUUAAAAGAGGUAAAUUUAUUGUAUGUAAAUUGUAUCUUAAUAAAACUGAUUAAAACAGACAUACAAACCCCA